ACAGCUAUGGGCUGGAGGCCCCGGAGAGCUCGGGGGACCCCGUUGCUGCUGCUGCUACUACUGCUGCUGCUCUGGCCAGUGCCAGGCGCCGGGGUGCUUCAAGGACAUAUCCCUGGGCAGCCAGUCACCCCGCACUGGGUCCUGGAUGGACAACCCUGGCGCACCGUCAGCCUGGAGGAGCCGGUCUCGAAGCCAGACAUGGGGCUGGUGGCCCUGGAGGCUGAAGGCCAGGAGCUCCUGCUUGAGCUGGAGAAGAACCACAGGCUGCUGGCCCCAGGAUACAUAGAAACCCACUACGGCCCAGAUGGGCAGCCAGUGGUGCUGGCCCCCAACCACACGGUGAGAUGCUUCCAUGGGCUCUGGGAUGCACCGCCAGAGGAUCAUUGCCACUACCAAGGGCGAGUAAGGGGCUUCCCCGACUCCUGGGUAGUCCUCUGCACCUGCUCUGGGAUGAGUGGCCUGAUCACCCUCAGCAGGAAUGCCAGCUAUUAUCUGCGUCCCUGGCCACCCCGGGGCUCCAAGGACUUCUCAACCCACGAGAUCUUUCGGAUGGAGCAGCUGCUCACCUGGAAAGGAACCUGUGGCCACAGGGAUCCUGGGAACAAAGCGGGCAUGACCAGCCUUCCUGGUGGUCCCCAGAGCAGGGGCAGGCGAGAAGCGCGCAGGACCCGGAAGUACCUGGAACUGUACAUUGUGGCAGACCACACCCUGUUCUUGACUCGGCACCGAAACUUGAACCACACCAAACAGCGUCUCCUGGAAGUCGCCAACUACGUGGACCAGCUUCUCAGGACUCUGGACAUUCAGGUGGCGCUGACCGGCCUGGAGGUGUGGACCGAGCGGGACCGCAGCCGCGUCACGCAGGACGCCAACGCCACGCUCUGGGCCUUCCUGCAGUGGCGCCGGGGGCUGUGGGCGCAGCGGCCCCACGACUCCGCGCAGCUGCUCACGGGCCGCGCCUUCCAGGGCGCCACAGUGGGCCUGGCGCCCGUCGAGGGCAUGUGCCGCGCCGAGAGCUCGGGAGGCGUGAGCACGGACCACUCGGAGCUCCCCAUCGGCGCCGCAGCCACCAUGGCCCAUGAGAUCGGCCACAGCCUCGGCCUCAGCCACGACCCCGACGGCUGCUGCGUGGAGGCUGCGGCCGAGUCCGGAGGCUGCGUCAUGGCUGCGGCCACCGGGCACCCGUUUCCGCGCGUGUUCAGCGCCUGCAGCCGCCGCCAGCUGCGCGCCUUCUUCCGCAAGGGGGGCGGCGCUUGCCUCUCCAAUGCCCCGGACCCCGGACUCCCGGUGCCGCCGGCGCUCUGCGGGAACGGCUUCGUGGAAGCGGGCGAGGAGUGUGACUGCGGCCCUGGCCAGGAGUGCCGCGACCUCUGCUGCUUUGCUCACAACUGCUCGCUGCGCCCGGGGGCCCAGUGCGCCCACGGGGACUGCUGCGUGCGCUGCCUGCUGAAGCCGGCUGGAGCGCUGUGCCGCCAGGCCAUGGGUGACUGUGACCUCCCUGAGUUUUGCACGGGCACCUCCUCCCACUGUCCCCCAGACGUUUACCUACUGGACGGCUCACCCUGUGCCAGGGGCAGUGGCUACUGCUGGGAUGGCGCAUGUCCCACGCUGGAGCAGCAGUGCCAGCAGCUCUGGGGGCCUGGCUCCCACCCAGCUCCCGAGGCCUGUUUCCAGGUGGUGAACUCUGCGGGAGAUGCUCAUGGAAACUGCGGCCAGGACAGCGAGGGCCACUUCCUGCCCUGUGCAGGGAGGGAUGCCCUGUGUGGGAAGCUGCAGUGCCAGGGUGGAAAGCCCAGCCUGCUCGCACCGCACAUGGUGCCAGUGGACUCUACCGUUCACCUAGAUGGCCAGGAAGUGACUUGUCGGGGAGCCUUGGCACUCCCCAGUGCCCAGCUGGACCUGCUUGGCCUGGGCCUGGUAGAGCCAGGCACCCAGUGUGGACCUAGAAUGGUGUGCCAGAGCAGGCGCUGCAGGAAGAAUGCCUUCCAGGAGCUUCAGCGCUGCCUGACUGCCUGCCACAGCCACGGGGUUUGCAAUAGCAACCAUAACUGCCACUGUGCUCCAGGCUGGGCUCCACCCUUCUGUGACAAGCCAGGCUUUGGUGGCAGCAUGGACAGUGGCCCUGUGCAGGCUGAAAACCAUGACACCUUCCUGCUGGCCAUGCUCCUCAGCGUCCUGCUGCCUCUGCUCCCAGGGGCCGGCCUGGCCUGGUGUUGCUACCGACUCCCAGGAGCCCAUCUGCAGCGAUGCAGCUGGGGCUGCAGAAGGGACCCUGCGUGCAGUGGCCCCAAAGAUGGCCCACACAGGGACCACCCCCUGGGCGGCGUUCACCCCAUGGAGUUGGGCCCCACAGCCACUGGACAGCCCUGGCCCCUGGACCCUGAGAACUCUCAUGAGCCCAGCAGCCACCCUGAGAAGCCUCUGCCAGCAGUCUCGCCUGACCCCCAAGCAGAUCAAGUCCAGAUGCCAAGAUCCUGCCUCUGGUGAGAGGUAGCUCCUAAAAUGAACAGAUUUAAAGACAGGUGGCCACUGACAGCCACUCCAGGAACUUGAACUGCAGGGGCAGAGCCAGUGAAUCACCGGACCUCCAGCACCUGCAGGCAGCUUGGAAGUUUCUUCCCCGAGUGGAGCUUCGACCCACCCACUCCAGGAACCCAGAGCCACAUUAGAAGUUCCUGAGGGCUGGAGAACACUGCUGGGCACACUCUCCAGCUCAAUAAACCAUCAGUCCCAGAAGCAAAGGUCACACAGCCCCUGACCUCCCUCACCAGUGGAGGCUGGGUAGUGCUGGCCAUCCCAAAAGGGCUCUGUCCUGGGAGUCUGGUGUGUCUCCUACAUGCAAUUUCCACGGACCCAGCUCUGUGGAGGGCAUGACUGCUGGCCAGAAGCUAGUGGUCCUGGGGCCCUAUGGUUCGACUGAGUCCACACUCCCCUGGAGCCUGGCUGGCCUCUGCAAACAAACAUAAUUUUGGGGACCUUCCUUCCUGUUUCUUCCCACCCUGUCUUCUCCCCUAGGUGGUUCCUGAGCCCCCACCCCCAAUCCCAGUGCUACACCUGAGGUUCUGGAGCUCAGAAUCUGACAGCCUCUCCCCCAUUCUGUGUGUGUCGGGGGGACAGAGGGAACCAUUUAAGAAAAGAUACCAAAGUAGAAGUCAAAAGAAAGACAUGUUGGCUAUAGGCGUGGUGGCUCAUGCCUAUAAUCCCAGCACUUUGGGAAGCCGGGGUAGGAGGAUCACCAGAGGCCAGCAGGUCCACACCAGCCUGGGCAACACAGCAAGACACCGCAUCUACAGAAAAAUUUUAAAAUUAGCUGGGCGUGGUGGUGUGUACCUGUAGGCCUAGCUGCUCAGGAGGCUGAAGCAGGAGGAUCACUUGAGCCUGAGUUCAACACUGCAGUGAGCUAUGGUGGCACCACUGCACUCCAGCCUGGGUGACAGAGCAAGACCCUGUCUCUAAAAUAAAUUUUAAAAAGACA